GUAGAAGAAACAUCACUCAGAUCUCUGCCUUUUAUCUUCACAUGGUGUUCCUGUGUAUGCGCCCAGUUUUCCUCUUUUUAUAAGGACACCAUAAAAAGCUAAGAAGUGCAAAAGAAGAAAAAAAGAAUAAACCAAAGACGCCAGUCAUAUUGGAUUAGGGACCAAUCUAUUUCAGCAUGGCCACAUCUUAACUAAUUAUAUCUCCAAUGACCCUAUUUCCAAAUAAGGUCAUCUUCUGAGCAAAACUCACUGACAUUUCCCAUCAGUGGUUAAUCAGUCAAAAACAUAUAGAAUGACAGCAAAAAUUAAAGAUAAGCAAGAUAAUGAAGAAAUAUGUUUUGCAAUCCUGUUGAAGACAGAAUAAGCAAAAGUGACCAAGAGAAACAGAUUCACCAAGUCUGUUGAUUGAUUUAAAGUGGAUUUAUGUUUAAGUAGAAAACCACUCCAAAAGCAUACUUUAGGGAAGAUGUCAGCUCCAAGAUUACUGAUUUCCAUCAUUAUCAUGGUGUCUGGCUGUACAGGAAGCAUGGCUGAGGAGGCCUCAAAAAACUUACAAUCAUGGUGGAAAUGUGAAGGGGAAGCAAGCAUGUCUUCAAAUGGCCAGCAGAAGCCUCAGAUAAUAAUUCCUGUCUGAUGACACAACUGGAAAUACAAAGUUAGAGAAUACGUCUUAAUGAAGCUUCAAGUAGUUCAUGCAUGGGUGGAAAGCAGAUGACACAGAACUAUUCAACAAUUUUUGCAGAAGGUAACAUUUCACAGCCUGUACUGAUGGAUAUAAAUGCUGUGCUUUGUUGCCCUCCUAUCGCAUUAAGAAAUUUGAUCAUAAUAACAUGGGAAAUAAUCCUGAGAGGCCAGCCUUCCUGCACAAAAGCCUACAAGAAAGAAACAAAUGAGACCAAGGAAACCAACUGUACUGUUGAGAGAAUAACCUGGGUCUCUAGACCUGAUCAGAAUUCGGACCUUCAGAUUCGUCCGGUGGACACCACUCAUGACGGGUAUUACAGAGGCAUAGUGGUAACACCUGAUGGGAAUUUCCAUCGUGGAUAUCACCUCCAAGUGUUAGUUACACCCGAAGUGAACCUAUUUCAAAGCAGGAAUAUAACUGCAGUAUGCAAGGCAGUUACAGGGAAGCCAGCUGCCCAGAUCUCCUGGAUCCCAGAGGGAUCUAUUCUUGCCACUAAGCAAGAAUACUGGGGCAAUGGCACAGUGACGGUUAAGAGUACAUGCCCCUGGGAGGGCCACAAGUCUACUGUGACCUGCCAUGUCUCCCAUUUGACUGGCAACAAGAGUCUGUCCGUAAAGUUGAAUUCAGGUCUCAGAACCUCAGGAUCUCCAGCGUUGUCCUUACUGAUCAUUCUUUAUGUGAAACUCUCUCUUUUUGUGGUCAUUCUGGUCACCACAGGAUUUGUUUUCUUCCAGAGGAUAAAUCAUGUCAGAAAAGUUCUUUAAAGAAGAAGGAAGGGUCUUCUUUUGCUUCUCCUCCUUGUCUCUGGACUGCAACAUUGGUGAGAUGAGUGAUGGUCCAGCAGUGAACUUGGGCCAUGGAUGAUGUUAAGGAUAGAAGCCACUCAGUAGGAUAGAAGAAAAGAAAGAUGGAAGAAGGAUCCUGGGCUUGAUGACCAUGAAGUUUCCCUAUAAACCCUCAACCACCUAUUCAUUGACUUCUUUUGUGUUAGAGUGAAUAAAAUUUUGUUCAUGCCA